CCACAAAUGUGGGAGGGCGAUAACCACUCGUAGAAAGCGUGAGAAGUUACUACAAGCGGUCCUCCCGGCCACCGUACUGUUCCGCUCCCAGAAGCCCCGGGCGGCGGAAGUCGUCACUCUUAAGAAGGGACGGGGCCCCACGCUGCGCACCCGCGGGUUUGCUAUGGCGAUGAGCAGCGGCGGCAGUGGUGGCGGCGUCCCGGAGCAGGAGGAUUCCGUGCUGUUCCGGCGCGGCACAGGCCAGAGCGAUGAUUCUGACAUUUGGGAUGAUACAGCACUGAUAAAAGCAUAUGAUAAAGCUGUGGCUUCAUUUAAGCAUGCUCUAAAGAAUGGUGACAUUUGUGAAACUUCGGGUAAACCAAAAACCACACCUAAAAGAAAACCUGCUAAGAAGAAUAAAAGCCAAAAGAAGAAUACUGCAGCUUCCUUACAACAGUGGAAAGUUGGGGACAAAUGUUCUGCCAUUUGGUCAGAAGACGGUUGCAUUUACCCAGCUACCAUUGCUUCAAUUGAUUUUAAGAGAGAAACCUGUGUUGUGGUUUACACUGGAUAUGGAAAUAGAGAGGAGCAAAAUCUGUCCGAUCUACUUUCCCCAAUCUGUGAAGUAGCUAAUAAUAUAGAACAGAAUGCUCAAGAGAAUGAAAAUGAAAGCCAAGUUUCAACAGAUGAAAGUGAGAACUCCAGGUCUCCUGGAAAUAAAUCAGAUAACAUCAAGCCCAAAUCUGCUCCAUGGAACUCUUUUCUCCCUCCACCACCCCCCAUGCCAGGGCCAAGACUGGGACCAGGAAAGCCAGGUCUAAAAUUCAAUGGCCCACCACCGCCACCGCCACCACCACCACCCCACUUACUAUCAUGCUGGCUGCCUCCAUUUCCUUCUGGACCACCAAUAAUUCCCCCACCACCUCCCAUAUGUCCAGAUUCUCUUGAUGAUGCUGAUGCUUUGGGAAGUAUGUUAAUUUCAUGGUACAUGAGUGGCUAUCAUACUGGCUAUUAUAUGUUUCCUGAGGCCUCCCUAAAAGCCGAGCAGAUGCCAGCACCAUGCUUCCUGUAAAGCCUGCAGAACCGUGAGUCAACUAAACCUCUUUUCUUUAUGAAAGAAAAGGAAGGAAGGGAGAGAGGGAAGGAGAAAAAGAGAGAGGGAGAGAUGGAUGGAGGAAGGGAGGGAGGGCUUACAACCAUGAGGACAGUUUUUAGGUCAAUGAGGGAUGACUUGGGAGUCCUAUGAAGACUGAUGUAAACUAGAAUAAAGGGCAUGAUGAGCUUAUGAUUCAAAAGUAUUUUGUCAUAGAAAUAGUUUGUUUUCUGUAAAAGAACACAGUAAAUAUUUUAGCUUUGUAGGCCACUGAGUCUCUGUUGCUUUAAAAAAUGUGAAAACCAUUCUUAGCUUGAGGGCUGGACAGUCCAGGGCCAUACUUUACUGACCGCUGCUUGAACUAAACGCUGUUAGAAGCAGCUCUGGAAAAAUAAUUUGCAUGGAAUCUUAUGAUUUUUUUUUUUUUUUUUUUUUUUUUGAGGCAGAAUUUUGCUCUUGUUGCCCAGGCUAGAGUGCAAUAGCGCGUUCUUGGCUCACUGCAACCUCCGCCUCCUGGGUUCAAGCAAUUCUCCUGCCUCAGCCUCCCGAGUAGCUGGGAUUACAGGAAGGCACCACCAUGCGUGGCUAAUUUUGUAUUUUUAGUAGAGACAAGGUUUCUCCAUGUUGGUCAGGCUGGUCUCGAACUCCCAACCUCAGGUGAUCCACCCGCCUCGGCCUCCCAAAGUGCUGGGAUUACCAGCGUGAGCCACUGCACCUGGUCAAGUAUCAUGGUUUUUUAAUAGUAUGCACACAUGGGACAAAACUCAACUGGUAUAAAAGGGUAUGCAGGAGAAAAAAAGCAAACUUCCCUCUCUCCCUUUUCUGUCCACCAGCCAUCCUGUUCUCCUCCCUAAACUCAAUUAUGGUUGCCUGUUUUUUAUAUAAGUUUUCCAUGAAUUUAUAAAUACAUCACGUGCAUAUAUCCUGUCAGUCAAUAUUAAGAAAUUACUAGGUUAUUUUGUGUUUAUGUGUGCACUAUUAGAUUUAAUGAGUUAUGCUAGUUGUUGCCUCUUAUAUCCACAUUCAGUCUUCAUUGUCUGUUCUGUAAUAAUAGAUCUGGGCCCUGUAAAUACCUCUCCCAUGACAGUAAGCACAGAGUGAAACUUUGUCAAUCGAGGGUGCUGCUGACACACUGAAGGGGCAAGGGCUGCUUUUCCUGGUUCCAUUGUGCUCCUCUAGGCAGACACCUGCAACACCUGUGCCAUCUGCAAUACCAGCUCCUGUAGCACAUACACUCUGCCUCUGCAGCACCUCGUUCUGGCUGCACACUUCUUGGGCGGUGCCUAACUUCAGCAGCACCCAAUGGUCAGCAGCGCACAGUACCCCCACAUGAAUGGCUUCCCUUGACAUGCACAAGGUCCCUUCUCUGCAAAGUGCCCCAAGCCCAGCACCUUCUCCAGCUGCAACUCCACAGCCUCAGCAAACCUCUGUCUUUCACAGCUGUGUCCUCUCACACGAAGUCUGGAUCUCAGCCCGGAUCUCAGCCCUGAGCUUUCUUCUUUGAGUUGUUCUGUCUCAGCCUGGGGUGAAAAGCCCAUAUCGGCUGUUCCCUGCAUCUGCCCAGGCUUCUCUUUAUUCCUUACUACCCAAUCCCCAUUCCAGUCCUCUGUUAAUAACUCUUACGGACAGUCCCCAACUCAUGAUGACUUGACUUAGGAUUUUUCUACUUUGCAAUGGUGCAAAAGUGAUCCGCAUUCAGUAGAAACUGUUCCUCAAGUACUCAUACGACCUCUAUUUUUCACUUUCUGUACAGUAUUCAAUAAAUUGCGUGAGAUUUUCAAUACUUUAUUAUAAAAUAGGCUUUGUGUUUAUGAUUUUGCCCAACUGUAAGCUAAUAUAAGUGUUCUCAGCGUGUUUAAGGUAGGUCAGGUUAAGCGAUGAUGUUUGGUAGUUUAGGUAUAUUAAAUGCAUUUCUGACAUACAAUAUUUUCUACUUACAAUGGGUUUUUCAGGAUAUAACCCUGUUGUAAGUUGAGGAGCAUCUUAUUUUAUUUAUUUAUUUAUUUAUUUGAAAUGGAGUCUUGCUCUGUCACCCAGGCUGGAGUGCAGUGGCACGAUCUUGGCUCACUGCAACCUCUGCCUCCUGGGUUCAAGCAAUUCUCCUGCCUCAGCCUCCCAAGUAGCUGAGACUACAGGUGCACACCACCAUGCCUGGCUUUUUUUUUUUUUUUUUAAUUUUUUUUUGUAUUUUUAGUAGAGACAGGAUUUCACCAUGUUGGCCAGGCUGGUCUCGAACUCCUGACCUCAAGUGAUCUGCCCACCUCGGCCUCCCAAAGUGCUGGAAUUACAGGCGUGAGCCACUGCGUCAGGCCGAGCAUCUGUAUAUUAAACUUUCCCCAUUCAAAUUUCUGUGUGGUUUCUGUCUCCUGACUGGAUUCUGAUAUAAUGCUUAACAACCUUUCUAAUUACAAAGGUAUUACAUAUAAAAUCAGACAAGCAAGAAGACAAUCCAUCCCACCUUCUAGUACUCUUGCCCUCCAGAGGUAGCUCCAGUUAAUAUUUUAGUGCUAAACUAGAUUUAUUUUUGUUUUAAAUAGAAAAAUAAUGCAGGCACGAAAGUAAAACAAAAAACAGUACAGAAUGGGAGAGACUGAAAAGUAAGAAUGGCUUCCAGGCCCACUUCCUAGAGGUACGCACUAUUAACAUUUUUAGAUAUAAACUUCCAGAAAUUUUUUUCCAGUUUUAUUUAGGUAUAAUUGACAAAAUUAUUUAUAUUUCAGUUGUACAACAUGGAUGUUCAACAUGUUUUGGUGUACAUAUACUUUCUGAUAUUAUAAAUGGUUACCACAAGCAAGCUCAGUAACAUAUUCAGAAAUUCUUAAUGUAGCUAGCAAUAUAAGUGGUUUUGUUUUUUGUUUUGAGACAGACAGGGUCUUGCUCUGUUGCCCAGGCUGGAAUGCAGUGGCGCCAUCUUGGCUCACUGCAACCUCUGCCUCCCGGGUUCAAGCAAGUCUUGCGUCUCAGCCGCCCUAGUGGCUGGGACUACAGGCAUGUGCCACCACACCUGGCUAAUUUUUGUAUUUUUAGUAGAGAUGGGGUUUCACCAUGCUGGCCAGGCUGGUCUCGAAUUCCUCACCUCAAAUGAUUCGCCCGCCUCAGCCUCCCAAAGUGCUGGGAUUACAGGUGUGAGCCACCGCACCCAGUCAUAAGUGGUUUUCUAAACAAAUGAGACCACACCAUACAUACUGUCCCUAUAUUUCAUACUUGGGCAAGGGGAGGGGAGUUGACUUUUUUCUUAGUGAGAAUAAAAAUGAGGAUAAAAGUAUGGUUGUUUACCAACUUAUAGUAGUAUCAUGAAUUUCGAAUGGUCUUCUGGCCGUUCAGAAAACUACUUAACUGGUAGGAACGAAAUUCUGGACACUGACAUUGAUAUAGACACUCAUAUCAAAUAUAAUACUAUGAAAUACUAUGAUAUGGAAAUAAUAUGCAAUCACUAGAGAUAAAAUAUUUUCUACCCAAGUAGAGUGGAUUCAUAAGAAAAUUCUAAAUUAUAGCAUAUGUUGAACUCUGAGAAGCCUCUGGAAUGAAGUCAUUUUUCCCUAACCCCUGUUUCCUCUUUAUAUUGGCAGUGGAUAAAUGGAAAGUAAGUUAACUCUACUGUACCAAAGCUAGUUCAAUAUAGAAAACAGGUUCUACAAGGAUUAAGGAACAUCUCUUGGCCCACAGAAGAUUCAUGUGGAUCCUGUGUUAAACCCGUUUCAUCCAUGUAUGAAAGUGAUUCAACCGUUAAGUUAGCCAUUUAUUAUAUAAAUUGAAUACUUCUUCCAUAUUGUGGCUUUUAGAUAGAUUGGCAGACCUGUCCCCAACCCCUUCCCUGUUGACCAUGGACAAUGGAGGGUUUGCUGUAUAAACUUGAUUGAAGGGUUUGCCUUUAGCUGGGGUGGAUUACUCAGGGACCUCAAAGGUAUUGGUGAUGAUUUAUUUCUUGAGCUUGGUGGUGAGUAUGCAGGACUGUGUUUUGUUUUGUUUUGUUUUUUAGCAAGCCUUACACAUUUUCUUUUGUAUGCAAUAUUUAAUAAAAUAAUUUUGGAUAAUUUGGUUUUUAGCAUUAAUCAACAACUUUUUUUACAUCCUCAAUAUGCCCCAAGACAAAUUAUUGAUUCAGCAGUUUUUAGCUGAAUCUUUUAUUUCUGAAUGAUUGGAGAGAACGGCAGUAUCCAUUUCUGGAGAAUAGUUAAGUACUUAGAUUGAGGAUGUCUUUCUUUCAUGACAUUAAGCAAUGCAAUAUCAUCUGCAUCCAAGAGCCAACUUAACAUGUUCAGUCUAAUGAGCCUUGGUAGUCGUAACACACAUUGACUCAAAGACUUGACUGUUGUGGCCUGAGCUUUGAUACACUCUGUGAAAUGCCUGGAGAUGUCCAACUCCUGCAAGUUUGGCAUGUUGUCCAGUGCUUGAAAGAAAUUUCUGUAUCCUUCCUCUGUAAUCUUGUGAUUGAUUGAAAGCUUUAGGUUCUCAAGUUUCUGGAAACCUCCACUGAUUGCUACUUUGGCUACAAGAACAAAACAUUCAUGAAAAUAGAAUCAUAAGGACUUCCAUUUCAAUAAUGGUAGACAAGGUUAUUUGAACCAGCCUCCUCUCCCACCACUACUGCUAGUAGGAAGUACUCAAUAUAAUUUUGUUUUUUGAAAUGGGGUCUUGCUAUGUUAACACAGGCUGGUCUCUUUUUCUUUCUUUCUUUUUUUUUUUUUUUUUUUUUUUUUUUUGAGAUGGAGUCUCGCUCUGUUACCCAGGCUGCAGUGCAGUGGCAUGAUCUCAGCUCACUGCAACCUCCGCCUCCCAGGUUCAUGCCAUUCUCCUGCCUCAGCCUCCCGAGUAGCUGGGACUACAGGCGCCCGCCACCAUGCCCAGCUAAUUUUUUGUAUUUUUAGUAGAGACGGGGUUUCACUGUGUUAGCCAGGAUGGUCUCGAUCUCCUGACCUUGUGAUCCACCCGCCUUGGCCUCCCAAAGUGCUGGGAUUACAGGCGUGAGCCACCGCGCCUGGCCAUCACAGGCUGGUCUCAAACUCGUGGACUCAAGUGAUCCUCCUGCCUCAGCUUCCCAAGUAGGUGGGAUUACAAGCACGUGUCACUGUGCCCAGCUUAAUAUAAUAUUUUGAAAAUAUCUCCUUAAAAACCCCAAAGAGCUGAUGGGUUAAUAAAGAACCACCUGGCAAAAAUCUAAGGGAGAAGCAGAAACCAAAGAAGUACAGCCAAGCCUAAAGCACUGACGCCAUUGUGCUGAGAGUUUCACCAUCCUGGACAAAUAUGAGCUUCUCUUUUGGUCUCACAGGAGGUCACAUGCCAAGGUACAUCAUGCCUACAAACCAGACUAAAUUGGCAAGUCACAGUGGCUCACGCUUGUAAUCCCAGCAUUUUGGGAGGCCGAGGUGGGUAGAUCACUUGAAGUCAGGAGUUCGAGACCAGGCUGGCCAACAUGGUGAAACCCCAUCUCUACUAAAAAUACAAGAAUCAGCCGGAUAUGGUGGUACAUGCCUGUAAUCCCAGCUACUCGGGAGGCUGAGGCAGGAGAAUCAGCUUGAACCUGGGAGGUAGAGGUUGCAGUGAGCCAAAAUCCCACCACUGCACUCCAGCCUGGGUGACAGAGCAAGACUCCGUCUAAAAAACAAAAAGAGAAAACAAAAAAAAAAAAAUCCAGACUAAAUUACAAGGGACUUCAAAGAGUGUAGCAAUUAUGUCUUCCCCUUU